AUGACCAUUUCGGGGUUCUCCGUGGCGGGGAGCUCCGCCGCCGCCGUCCCCCUUCCACGCGCGGGAGGUCGGCGAGGGCAGGGCGGGGACCCGGAGUGCGGCCCCCGGUCCUGCUUCGAAAGGGAAGUCGAGAGGAGGCUGAGCGAACGGCCGCCACCCCCGCGGGACGCUGACCCGGGCGGACCCCGAGGGGCCUCUCCCCGCGCCAGAGCGCGGCGUGCGCGGGGAAGCGCGACCCACCGGGGUCGGCGACGGCGCGCGGGGCGGGCGCGGCGGUUCCCUCUCCUCCGCCCGUGCCCGUGGGAUCGGCGGGCUUGUCGGGCUGGGAGAGCCUCGUGGAACCCGGGCAUCCGGGCAGCAGCGGCCUCCGAGCCACUGUGGAGGCGCCCGGGGUCGGCACGGCGAGGCCGACGGGGACCUGACACGGUCACGCGGCGCCGGGGAGCAGGUUCGAGUGGCCGGGCGUGGCCGUGCUGCCCCUCCGCGUUCCGCAGGCGGCGACGGGCGAGCGGCCCUAGCGGGCUGCAGGGAGGACGCCGCGUGGACGGAGAGCCGGCGCCCGGGGGCCAGAUCCCCUCCCGGGACGGGGCGCCAGGUCCCCGCGAGCUGCGGCGCGACGCGCGGGCACCCGUGUCCCACCCGGUGGCCUCGCCGCUGCGGGCUGCGCUGAGAGCGGGGUGGCGCGACGCGGUCCCUCACCGCAGGGGGAAGACGGCACCACCGCGUCCCGGCCGCUGGAGCUUCCCGCCCGCGCCGCCGGCCCGACGCUGCCCCCUGGCGGGAGAGCGCUGCAGGGGCCCCGGCGAGGCCGCAGGACCCGACCUCCCCGCCGGCCUCGCACUCCCGCGCCGCCGCCGAGGGUCGGCAGCCGGAUCGCCCUCCGUGCCCCAUAGCACCCCUCACACUAAAAACGACGACUUUAUUAAGAUGUGAGAUACAGGGUCUCUGUCGCCCAGGCUGGAGUGCGGUGGCACGAUCUCGGCUCACCGCAGCCUUGAACUUCUAGGCUCCAGCGAUCCUCCUGCCUCAGCCUCCCGAGCAGCUGGGACCACAGGCCCCGCCACCAUGCCCGGCUCAGUUCCAUGACUUCUGACACGCGAAACCACCAGGCUAGUCUCCCCCCGAGUUCAAGAAGUCCUCUCCUCCCAAAAGUACCCUCCUGCCCCUCUGCAGCUAACCCCUCACCUCCCCUCCGCCCUGGUUCCAGACAACUGCUCCUCUGAUUUCUGUCACUGCCCUUUGCCUCUCUCGCAAUUGCAUGCAAGGAGAACCAUUCACCGUGUGGUCUUUUGUGCCUGGCUUUCUUCGCUUGGCACCAUGCAGCUGAGCGUCGCCCGUGUGGCGUGUGUGUGUUGUAUUUUCCUCUACCUUGGUCUUGAGACCUCCCUGGAGAGCCACUGUAAAGGCCAACUCUGCCCUGACAGGGCUCCUGGGAUUUGGGCGUGGGUGUUUGCCGUGGGCCUUUCAUGGGGCACCUCUGUAUCCUGGCUGACCUGUGACCGGGUGUCCCUCUCCCAGGAGACAUAUUUAUCCUGGCAGAUCUCCUUGUGCUUCUUGUCUGACCUGUAUCUAGUUUAUUCCUACCAAGAUAGCUGCUCUCUAGGGAAAGCCCUGACCAGGGAAAACGUUACGUUUGAGCGUCUCAGUCAGGCAUGACACAGAGCAGGCAACACAACGAAACACAGGAACUAACAGAAGUGGUCCUAUUACUUACAGAUCCACAGGGGAAGAGGGCACACUGAGGGCCGUCGGGAAUGUCUUGGGGACACUGUACACAAUCGUUGUGGGGGUGGGGGGAGCCAGAGAGAGACGGACCUGUGGGCUGAGGCUUUUAUUGGAGUGCAGGGCAUUACUCAAGCAGUUUUCCCAAGGGGAGCUCUAAUUGGUUCACCUAGAGGAGCGAACUGGAGUCCUGUGGGGCCACCUUGUGACUUAGGGGUGGUCACUGAGACAUAUCUGCAUAGUCCAUGCAGGGUGUGGGCGUCAGUGGGGUGAGUCUAGUUGGUUGUAUGUAUACAUCCCACAAGGAGGCAGUUACCAGGAGGUGGCUACCUAGGACCAGAUAUCUGGACGGAAUGUGUUGAGAUACUGUUUCCAGCAGAGAGCUGGAAACUGUAUCCAAGGUGACUAAGCCCUGCUUCUAGUAUGAAAUUGUUAACCCUAUAUUCAAAAUGGAUACUGAAGCAACCUAAAAUUUCAGGUAUUUACUAAAGUGUGUAUCAAGUUCCCUCCUUACCACUGGUGAGUAGUAUUCCAUUGUAUGGAUAUGCCACAGGCUGUUUGUCCAUUUGGACAUUGAUGGAUGGACUAAAGUUGGCCAAGCUGGGCUGGUGGGGAGGCACCCUCUCAGGACCCCAAAGGAGGAUGCGGGGUUGUUGUUGGAUGUCUGGGUUGUUUCCAGUUUGAAGGCAUUGUGAAUAAAACUGACUUGAGCCUUCCUAGAAA